GUGCGACAGGCCGAGGAGGGGCCGGGCGGGCGGGCAGCUCCGUGGGUCUCACUGCCCUGAGAAGGCCGGCGCUGCUGCCCACCCCCAGGGACGAAGGGGUGGUGAUUCGUUUAUUCAGGUGUUCAUGGCGCGUCUGCUUGUGCCAGGCAUGUUGUAGGCCCUGGGGCCCUGUGGGGAACAGUAGGGCCCCUGUUCCCGUAGCUUACCUGAUAUGUGGAGAAGAACGAUAAACAACGCUGACGGUGGUGACGUCUUCUUCCCUGCCUCUCUGUGAGAAUCAGCUGGGAAAUGGCUCAUCGCAGAGGAUUGGAAGGGCCUAGAUUACUGCCCAAUGACAAAAGUGUGGGCUUAAUGUCCUCACUCUUCAGGGAGAGAAUGUGGACUUUAGCAUUUGAACUGAAUAUUUGAGAUUGAAGAUUUCUGAAUACAUUCCCAAAGUCAGAAAUAUUUUAUCUUGAAGGGCAUGAAACGAAAUAGCACCAAAACAAAUGCUCCCAAAGGCAGCAGCACCCUCUCAGGCAGUACCAAAGCCAGGGAUUUAAUGUGCAAAAUGGCGAUUAUACCAGACUGGCUUAGGUCGCAUCCUCACACACGAAAAUUUACACAUUCAAGACCCCAUUCUUCACCGUGUAGAGUAUAUUCAAGGAAUGGUUCCCCAAAUAAGUUCAGAUCUUCUUCAACCACAGCUGUUGCAAAUCCAACACUGUCCUCCUUAGAUGUUAAACGGAUUUUAUUUCAAAAAAUUACCGACAGAGGGGAUGAGUUGCAAAAAGCCUUUCAGCUGCUGGAUACUGGUCAGAACUUGACUGUGUCAAAAAGUGAACUGAGAAGAAUCAUCACAGACUUCCUGAUGCCGCUCACACGAGAACAGUUUCAGGACGUGUUGGCUCAGAUCCCCCUUAGCACCUCUGGUACUGUACCGUACCUUGCCUUUCUGUCCAGGUUUGGUGGAAUUGACCUAUAUAUAAAUGGUAUAAAGAGGGGAGGUGGGAAUGAAAUGAAUUGCUGCCGCACAUUAAGAGAACUUGAAAUCCAAGUGGGAGAAAAGGUUUUCAAAAACAUUAAGACUGUUAUGAAAGCCUUUGAGCUCAUUGAUGUUAACAAGACUGGACUGGUUCGACCGCAGGAGCUAAGAAGGGUUCUGGAGACCUUCUGUAUGAAGUUAAGAGACGAGGAAUACGAAAAGUUUUCGAAACACUACAACAUCCACAAGGAUACUGCAGUAGAUUACAACGUGUUUUUGAAGAAUCUCAGCAUAAAUAACGACUUGAACCUUAGAUAUUGUAUGGGAAAUCAAGAGGUCUCGUUGGAGAAUCAACAAGCCAAAAAUUCCAAAAAGGAACGUUUGCUAGGUUCUGCAUCAUCUGAAGAUAUCUGGAGAAACUACUCCUUGGAUGAAAUUGAGAGGAACUUUUGUCUACAACUUUCGAAGUCUUAUGAAAAGGUUGAAAAGGCCCUCAGUGCAGGGGACCCCUGUAAAGGUGGCUACGUGUCUUUUAAUUAUCUAAAGAUUGUCCUCGACACUUUUGUAUACCAAAUACCAAGAAGAAUUUUUAUCCAGUUAAUGAAAAGAUUUGGACUUAAAGCCACCACUAAAAUCAAUUGGAAGCAAUUUCUAACAUCAUUUCAUGAGCCUCAGGGGUUGCAAGUUAGCAGUAAAGGUCCCCUGACAAAAAGAAAUAGCAUCAACUCUAGAAAUGAAUCUCACAAGGAAAACAUCAUCACAAAGUUAUUUAGACACACUGAAGAUCACUCUGCGUCACUGAAGAAAGCAUUACUGAUAAUCAACACUAAACCCGAUGGACCGAUAACAAGAGAAGAAUUUCGAUAUAUUCUAAAUUGCAUGGCUGUAAAACUAAGCGAUUCAGAAUUCAAAGAACUAAUGCAAAUGCUUGACCCUGGGGACACUGGAGUGGUCAACACCAGCAUGUUUAUUGAUCUGAUUGAAGAGAACUGUAGGAUGAGAAAGACAUCUCCCUGUACAGAUGCUAAGACACCUUUCCUCCUGGCCUGGGAUUCAGUGGAAGAAAUUGUUCAUGAUACAAUUACUAGGAACCUACAAGCUUUUUAUAACAUGCUACGCUCAUAUGACCUUGGAGACACAGGGCGCAUUGGCCGAAAUAAUUUCAAGAAAAUCAUGCACGUCUUCUGUCCAUUUUUAACGAAUGCACAUUUCAUAAAACUCUGCAGUAAGAUUCAGGACAUUGGUUCAGGAAGAAUCCUUUACAAGAAACUUUUGGCAUGCAUAGGAAUUGAUGGCCCACCCACUGUCUCUCCAGUUCUUGUUCCAAAGGAUCAGCUGUUAAGUGAACAUUUACAAAAAGAUGAACAGCAGCAGCCAGAUCUUUCUGAGAGAACCAAGCUCACGGAGGAUAAAACCACCCUGACCAAGAAGAUGACCACAGAAGAAGUGAUUGAAAAAUUCAAAAAGUGUAUACAGCAGCAGGACCCGGCAUUCAAAAAACGAUUUCUUGACUUCAGCAAGGAGCCUAAUGGAAAAAUUAACGUGCAUGACUUUAAGAAGGUACUGGAAGACACUGGGAUGCCCAUGGACGAUGAUCAGUAUGCCCUGCUGACCACUAAAAUAGGCUUCGAGAAGGAAGGGAUGAGCUAUCUUGAUUUUGCAGCAGGAUUUGAAGAUCCUCCAAUGAGAGGGCCGGAAACCACUCCGCCGCAGCCUCCAACUCCUUCAAAAAGUUACGUGAACAGCCACUUUAUCACCGCAGAAGAAUGCCUGAAGCUUUUCCCUAGGAGGCUGAAGGAGUCAUUCCGGGACCCCUACUCUGCCUUCUUUAAAACAGAUGCUGACAGGGAUGGCAUAAUCAACAUGCAUGACCUUCACAGACUGCUCCUGCAUCUACUGCUUAAUCUCAAAGACGACGAGUUUGAGCGCUUCCUUGGCCUUCUUGGCUUGAGACUUAGUGUCACUUUAAAUUUUCGGGAAUUUCAAAAUUUGUGUGAGAAGAGACCAUGGAGAACAGAUGAAGCGCCUCAAAGACUCAUUAGACCAAAACAGAAGGUUGCGGAUUCAGAACUAGCUUGUGAGCAGGCUCAUCAGUAUCUUGUUACCAAAGCAAAAAACAGAUGGUCAGACUUGUCUAAGAAUUUUCUAGAAACCGAUAAUGAGGGCAAUGGCAUUCUUCGACGCCGGGACAUAAAGAACGCACUGUACGGUUUUGAUAUUCCCCUCACACCAAGAGAGUUUGAAAAGCUUUGGGCAAGAUACGACACCGAGGGAAAAGGGCACAUUACUUACCAGGAAUUUUUACAGAAAUUGGGUAUUAACUAUUCGCCUGCUGUCCAUCGGCCCUGUGCAGAGGAUUAUUUCAACUUCAUGGGUCAUUUUACAAAGCCACAGCAGCUACAGGAAGAGAUGAAGGAGCUGCAGCAGAGCACAGAGAAGGCUGUGGCAGCCAGGGAUAAGCUUAUGGACCGCCAUCAAGAUAUCAGCAAAGCAUUCACCAAAACUGAUCAAUCCAAAACCAACUACAUAUCCAUAUGCAAGAUGCAGGAAGUGCUGGAAGAAUGUGGAUGUUCUCUUACCGAAGGGGAGCUGACCCAUCUGCUAAACAGUUGGGGAGUCAGCCGGCAUGAUAAUGCUAUCAAUUACCUCGACUUCCUGAGAGCAGUGGAGAACAGCAAGUCAACAGGAGCUCAGCCCAAGGAAAAAGAAGAGAGCAUGCCAAUCAAUUUUGCAACGCUGAAUCCACAGGAGGCUGUGAGGAAGAUCCAGGAAGUAGUUGAGUCCUCCCAGCUGGCUUUGUCCACGGCAUUUUCUGCAUUGGAUAAAGAGGAUACAGGAUUUGUAAAGGCUACAGAAUUCGGACAAGUUCUUAAGGAUUUCUGUUACAAACUAACGGACAAUCAGUAUCAUUAUUUUUUGAGGAAACUAAGAAUUCAUCUAACCCCCUAUAUAAAUUGGAAAUAUUUUCUCCAGAACUUUAGCUGUUUCCUUGAGGAGACAGCUGAUGAGUGGGCUGAGAAAAUGCCCAAAGGCCCGCCGCCUACCUCUCCCAAGGCCACAGCCGACAGAGACAUCCUGGCUCGCCUCCACAAAGCAGUGACUUCCCAUUACCAUGCCAUCACCCAGGAGUUUGAGAAUUUUGACACCAUGAAAACGAACACCAUCUCCAGAGAGGAGUUUAGGGCCAUUUGUAAUCGCCGCGUCCAAAUCCUGACGGACGAACAGUUUGACAGACUCUGGAACGAGAUGCCAGUCAAUGCCAAGGGGAGGCUGAAAUACCCGGACUUCCUGAGCAGGUUCAGUUCCGAGACAGCAGCCACACCAAUGGCCACUGGUGACUCGGCCGUGGCCCAGAGAGGGAGCAGUGUCCCUGACGUCUCGGAAGGCACCAGAUCUGCCCUCUCAUUGCCCACUCAGGAGCUGAGACCAGGGUCAAAGUCGCAGAGCCACCCCUGUACUCCAGCGAGCACCACCGUGAUCCCGGGCACUCCACCCUUGCAGAACUGUGAUCCCAUAGAGAGCAGGCUCCGGAAGAGAAUCCAGGGCUGCUGGCGCCAGCUCCUGAAAGAAUGCAAGGAGAAGGACGUGGCCAGACAGGGGGACAUCAACGCCUCCGAUUUCCUGGCUCUUGUGGAGAAAUUCAACCUGGACAUAAGCAAAGAGGAGUGUCAGCAGCUCAUUAUAAAAUACGACUUAAAGAGCAACGGGAAAUUUGCAUACUGUGACUUCAUUCAGAGCUGUGUCCUCCUGCUAAAAGCAAAGGAAAGCUCACUGAUGCACAGGAUGAAGAUCCAGAAUGCACACAAGAUGAAAGAAGCCGGCGCGGAGACGCCAUCUUUUUACUCUGCUCUGCUGCGUAUUCAGCCCAAAAUUGUGCACUGCUGGAGGCCAAUGCGGCGCACGUUCAAAAGCUAUGAUGAGGCUGGAACAGGGCUGCUAAGCGUCGCAGAUUUCAGGACGGUGAGCACAGCUCUGCGCCCAGUGCCUCUGCAGGGAGCAGCUGCCAAAUGCCAGCGGCCAGAAACUUCCCACGGGGAGCCCUCUACCUGCUGCCGAAGGCCCGGUGUGACCUGGCUGCUUCAGAUCUCACUUCCCUGGGACCCCCAAGUUAUCCAGUCCUGGGUCCACUCGCCUCACCUUCAGACCCCGGGUUCUCCUUCCCAAAGGUUGCUGGAGCCCUGCGUGGAUGCCCCAUACCUGCAUCGCCAGCUCCUCAGGGUCCUGAGACAGUACAGCAUCAACCUCUCUGAGGAAGAGUUCUUCCAUAUUCUGGAGUAUUACGAUAAGACGCUGUCUUCAAAAAUCUCCUACAACGACUUCCUCCGGGCAUUCCUCCAGUAGACACCCCUGCUGUGUGCCCAGCGGGACGACAGCCACAGGGCCUGUUUCAAGGCUAAUAAAAUCCUAUAAUUUGGG